AUUCGUGGCGACGGCGGCGGCAGGGACAGCAGGAGCAGUGGUGCUGUCAGCGCGGCCGUCGGAGACAUGGGAGACCCGGGGUCGGAGAUAAUAGAAUCUGUCCCUCCAGCUGGCCCUGAGGCAUCUGAGUCAACAACGGAUGAAAAUGAAGACGACAUUCAGUUUGUCAGUGAAGGACCAUUACGACCUGUUCUUGAAUACAUUGAUCUGGUCAGCAGUGAUGAUGAAGAGCCUAGCACCUCUUAUACUGAUAGAAUGCCUGAAUCUAAGGUGCCAUCCUCUGAGAAUCAUCGCCCAGAAAUGUGCUCUAGCUGCAAUGUUCCUCUUCCCAUUGGAGAUAGCAGCUCCUUCUCUGGGAGUUGUUCCAGCAGUCCAGAAAGGAUAGUUUCUCAAACUUCCUCUGUUGAGAACCCAUUGGAGAACCAGAAAAAUGAUCAAAAUAAUUCAGAUACUAAGAUCUCUGAGACAGAGACCCUUAAAUCAUCACAGAAUUUUCAGACUCUGCCUUCAUCUCCACUUCUGGUCCCCCAAGAAUCUUUGGCCUCUUCUGAGGUCAAAGAGAAUUUACGUAUAGAUUCUUCUUCAGCUUCACAGCAUGGACGGGAUGCCAUCCUCUAUCUCCAGACACAAGUAGCUGAAAUGUCCCGAGUGAUACGUGAUCUGCAGUCCAGGAGCUGUUUUAGAUUUCAUCAUUCUAGGCCAAGUGAGAACUCCUCAGUUCCUUGGGACAUCUCCACCUCUAAAGAGGAAAAUUUAUCCACAGUUGAAGAAGAAACUGAUUACAAAUCACCAUCAGCUGAUGACAAAGGGCAGCCAUCUGACCCCAGCCAAUCUAGUUUCACAGGUCUUUUGAAGAGAAUGGAACAAAGAGGUGUUAUAAAAAGGGUGACAUUACAAUCUGAAGCGGAGUCAUGUGAAGGGAAACCUGAUUGUGUGACUUCUAAAAAACGUUUGGUUCCUCCAUUGCAUCCUCUUCUGAGAAUUGCCACCACUGAGGUUUUUAAAGACCCUGCUGAUUGCCAUCCUUCUUCCUUCAUGGGACACAGGGUAUAUCCUGUGGCCAAGGACACCUCUCCUUUCCAACCAAACCCACCAGCUGAAGGCCCCAUUGUAGAAGCAUUAGAACACAGCAAAAGAGGAAACACAACAUCCCCUCUAGAUUCUACCUCAAAAGAAAUGGAGGUCAUGGGUUGUAGGUUUUACCACGCUGCCUCCAUUGCAGCCCGAGCUGCUAGCUACAUGGCCUAUAUGACUCAAUAUCAGCGUAAACUCUGGGAAGACAUGGAAGAUCUGGUUCAUGACCCAGAAUUUGAUCGUGGAAAAGCAAGAUGCAUAAUAUCUGAUGGUAUGGAUGCAGGCCUUUGGCAACUUUGUACUACUAGGGACAUAAUGGACUCUGUAGUCAGAGUUAUGGCCAUGGCCAUAGACUAUAGACGGCAGGCCUGGCUUCGACUUACAUCUCUCACUAAGAAAACCCAGGAGAAGAUCUCCCACUUGCCCUUUGAUGGUACUUCCCUUUUUGGACAAGAUGUGAAAGCUGUUGUUGCAGAAGACAACAAUAUAAAAGAAAAUGACUAUAAAGAUCACAAAUACUAUAAUCAGCAUCGAUACUUUUAUAGUCAUGAUCAGAAAGCACAUUAUCACAAUAGAGGAUACUCCAAAGGGGAUUGGUACAAACCUCGAAACCACCCCUAUAGAUAUAGAAAGAAGGGAGACUCUCCAGAACGCCAUGGGUACAAGAAUUAAUAACCUGUUUAAUGUUCAGCAGAGUAGUCAUUCAAGAUCCUAACUAUUUUACUUGUUCCUCCUUGUACAAAUAGGAUCUACAGGUAGGAGAUCAUCUCAAAAACUGGAUGCAUGUCUGGAAUGAUCACAGCUGACAUUUGAAUUCUAGACUUUUGAAAUGAAGUAUAUAAUAAAGAAACUCAUGACUUAUUGGCCAAGUGAGCAGUGGAGACUUUCUUGAAAGGGUUGGACAAAUGUUUAUCCUUUAUUUCUGGUCCAAAAAUAAGUGUGGAGGAGGACCACUCAGGAAUCUGAAUCCUCUUGUGAUUAAAGAAAAAUAUAAAGAUGUGUUCCUCAGGAAAAUCUUAUUUGUAAACUGAGGACUAGCAGAUUUUGAAUCUAGAAAUAAUACUAGAUGUCUGUUUACUAAGACCAGAGGUAAAUCCUUAACUUUUAGGUUAUCAGUGCUUCCUUGUUCAGGCUUCAGUUUGACAGAUCUUCACAAAAUGACACAUCUGUUAAAAUGUCUUUAUGUCAAGAUGGUCAACUCACCAAGAGUCCGUACUACUAUCAAGCUCUGUGAGACUUCAGAAUCAGCCAUGAAGCUUUGUGUCAACUGGAAUUCAAAUCAAAUUUUGCCAAAUCCAGUUUGCUUCCCCUUGGAAUGGCUAGAUGUCGCAGGUCUAUUAUGGACACCAACUGGAAAAAGACUUCUACCUGUAACAUCUCUGUAGAAAUUGCACAGUAACUAUCUUCAUCAAGACUUUGAUGGCCACCAUACCAUCACUACUCAUAAAGCUACAUGUGAGAGAAUUGUUUGUUGUUAUCAAUCCUAAUAGUCUUUGACCUAUCAAGCUCUCGUAUCAAGCUGUAAGACUGAGUCAUGGUAGUCUCUCACUGUAAGCUGGGCCUUUCACCAAGAUGGCCUUCUUAAACAACCUACCUUCUAAACAUUUAAUUCUUUUGAGCUUGAUAGUGCAUCACACUCUAAAUACAAAAAAGAUACGCACAUCAGUGCCCUGGAAAUAAAGGAUGUUACACGAUCCAGGCAUGCAAAUCUGAACUCCUAAGACCAAGAAUUCCAAACAUGCCUGACAAUCUUGUCCCCUUAUUGUAAUAAAGAGGGAUACCAUCAGUCUAGAUUUUAUUGAGAAUCCUUAAGAUUUAAAGCAUAGCUGUGGAUGUGGUGAAGAGAACAAGCCACACAGCUCUGUUUCUGGAUAUCUAAGUGAUGAUAUCCAUUAAUGAUUUGAAAGGCUGAAAUCAAGAUUUAAGUGAUACGCUCUUGGUUAAUUGGUUACUUAAUUUAGUCAGAUUCUUAGUGUAAGAGACAGCUUAUCUUUUUGCUCCCAAUUGGUCCCAUUAAUAGUUUUUCACCAUACUGGAACUGGCAGCAGAUACCUCAAUUAUAUGUCCCACAGUAUCUUCUCUUUAGACUCAAGGUAGUGGAUGUAUGGUAUAUCAGCCCUUAGAUCCAUGUCUUCACAGCAUGACAUCAGGAAUGGAGAAUAUGUCAAAUUUGAGGGGUCUGAAUACAUCACCUAGUAUUAUUUGCUUGGCAGCCAAAAACAGUUGUUUUUAUUGACAGACUUAAUUCUGUAACUUCUGCGUUUUUUCAUCUGCUUGAUCAAGGCAUUUUGGAUGUACUGCUAAUGGAAUAUGGCACUGUUUUACGGUUUAUGUGGCUUCUGUUCUUGCCACAGUUGUUGCACAGUGGUAAUUGAUGUUUUCUCUGGUGCCACACUUUUUAAUAAUCUAUUGGAAGCUCAUUCCUCCUCCCCCAUCAUAACCAUAUUCAGCACCCAUUUUUAAAUCUACUUUUCUUCCUUAUUUGUGCUACAGAGGUUGAUGGCGUAAAUUUUCCUACUUGGAAGAAAUUACUUUAUCAGUUAAUUUCAGGGUACUGUAUUGAUCUUGUUUGUCCUAUUUGUAGAUUAAACUUGAACUAGUCUUAAUAAAGGGGAUAUUGUUUUGCAAAUUUAGCCCAGUCAUAUCAAGAGUUAAUAUUUAUCUUAUUUUUCUGUAUUUUACUCAAAAUUUUAUUUCCACUUCUGUAGAAAUAGGUCCAUGCCAGUGUUCUCUACAAAGUGUCUUUCAAACUAAACUCUAGAAGAAUAUCGAUUACCUGAACAGAAACAAAGGCCUAAGAAAUCAUACAUUUUUGUAGCUUAUGUGUAUUGCACCAAUCAAGCAAUCCCAUGUGCUCUUGAUAUUGGCACUGUAGUUUUAUCUUAGAGGACUUGCCACUGGAGAACUCAGUGGUGAGAGACCUUGGAAAUGUUUUAUGUGGCUGCACAUAAGUGUUUCUGACUAGCUAAGGCUACUUCAGACUUUUCACUUUCCAUUUGUCCCCUUUUCCUUCCCUGAAUUAGAUGCUAUGUCAUAAACUUGGUGGUUUUUGAAAUACUCUUAUUUCAAACCUUAAACUAAACCGAAAUAAGUUAUGCCUGAGAAUGCGUUUGUCUGAAACGAUUUUGGCACUUCCCUUUAAUAUGCUUCCCCUUCCCUUUGCCUUUUAAAUUGUGGUUAAAAAAAAAGAAAAAAAAAGGCACAUAAAGCUGAGCACCUUAACCAUUUUUUAAGCGUAUGGUAGUGUUGACUAUAUUUGCAUUGUUGCGCAGCUCCUCCAUUCUUAAAUAUUUGUAAGAUGAUGUUGCUGUUCUCUUUUCCUCCUGUGAUAUUUAUGUUGCCCAGUAAUAAGUAAAAGUAUCCUUUCUUAGUUACUCUAACUGAUAUGCCCAAGUGUCUCCAGAUACUCUGUUUUCCUGGAAGUGUAAAGGUAUUGGGAAAUUAUCAAAUUGGUGACCAAGUAGUUCUGAAAGGAUUUGACCGUUUAAUAGGGAUGGGGACAGAAUGCAGAUCAGGAAGAGUUUUUAGUAAUAGAUUAGUUUCUUGAUUGCAAAAGAAAUAUCUUUAAUGUGUUAAUUUUUUAUUAUUUUAAAAUCUCUGGCAUACUUGAAUGAUAAUGUUAUAAAACUUAAAGUGAGGAUUUGGUCUAGGGAGAUUACCCCAAUAGAAUCAGAAACUCUUAGUCAGAUAAUAAAUCCUCAUAUUAUGCCUGCCAUGUUCAGAACCUGCAACAAAAUUCCCUACUAGGCCAACCUCUAACGUUUAAAUACCUCUAGGUUUUCUAGGAGGCCUUGGAAUAGUUGCAAGUUUAAUGAUCUGGUAUUCUCAAAAAGGAUGUAUCUAAUGAUCUUGAUUCUUCAAAAUGUUAUUUCUUGAUUAGAUAUACAAUGUAUAUAGAGACAAUAUGGUUUCUUGUAGUUACUGUGUAUAGAGAAGUACUGUUUCCAUUUUUAUAUGAAGUGCCUUUUUAAUUCUACACUUUUCUUUAAAACUUAAACUUUGAUGUCUUGCAUAUAUUGCUGGUGGUAUUUAUGUGAAUUUUGUACAGUGAUUUAAUCUUGUAGUUUAUCAUUUGUACAAUUGCACUAUCUAAAUGUACUCCCUUCUGAAUGUUAAUUUGUUUUCUUUAUAGCACUGUUGAUUCAUUUCAGAAGGUUGUAGAGUAUACCUCCCUCCCCCUUAUUUAACUAACUAGACAGUAGUUCCUUUUUGUUAUUAGUGAGUGGCUAAUUUUGGGGGGCCUUAAGGCAGCUUUGUUUUCUAUAGAUAUGCUCUAGGUUUUCUGAUUGUCUCGUAUCUAACCUUGUUCUUAGCCAUGAUAACACAACUUAUAUUUGAUAAGUGGAUGUGUUUACUUGGUUAGAAUAAGCAAGGACAUUUUUAAAAAGCAGUAAAUUUGCUGACACUUUUAUCUUUUUUUAAAAGAAUGAAUGACAGCUUCCUUAUCAGUAUAAUUACAUUUAAACUUUUUUUUUUAAACCGUGUGGCAGCUUCUUUAUCAAUCAGUAUAAUUCCAUUUAUUUACUUAGCCCUCAAAAUGACAUUUUGAAGGGAGCAUAAACUCUUUCAGGCUACUUGGACAGUAUUUAGUAUUCUAUAUUAGUACUACACUAAUAAUUUACUGAGUGCUACCUAAGUGACCUGAUUGAUAAUGUCCUUAAGGACCUGAUACAUCCAGGAUAACCUCUCAGGUACUGUAAACAAGGAGGUUGAAAAAGACACAUUCCGGAAUCCCUUUGUCUGGUAAAAUUGGAUACUGAUGUGGAUGGACAUGACAUUCAUUAUUCUUGAAGAUAUAACUAGUUGACUGGGAUUCUGAUGAAGGUUUGAAAUUAUGGAUUAGAUCUUUGUAGAAGUAGUUUAAAGAUUGCAAUAAGUGAAAUCUUUUUUUUUUUUUUUUUUUUGAGACAGUUUCGCUCUUGUUGCCCAGGCUGGAGUGCAAUGGCACGAUCUUGGCUGACUGCAACCGCCACCUCCCGGGUUCAAGCAAUUCUGUCUCAGCCUCCCGAGUAGCUGGGAUUACAGGCAUGUGUCACCAUGACCUGCUAAUUUUGUAUUUUUAGUAGAGACGGGGUCUCUCCAUGUUGGUCAGGCUGGUCUCAAACUCCUGACCUCAAGUGAUCCGCCCGCCUUGGCCUCCCAAAGUGCUGGGAUUAUAGGCGUGAGCCACCGCGCCUGGCUGUGAAAUUUUUUUUUUUUUUUUUUUUAUGUGAGGCAUAUUUUGCCACAGUCUCGCACUGUUUAGGUUCUCUUGUCUUUUGGAAUCUAUCAUUCUGUAUUUAAUGUUAGUGGCUAGUCCAAUAAUUGAUUGUCUCAUCUGUAUGCAUCUUAUGCAUGUGAUUCAAUAGACUAGAUCGAUUCUGUGUGGUUUAUCAUAGUAGAUACACAAACCAGUCUUUAUUUUUUACUUAAGAAAAUAUAUAAGUGGAAGUUAUCAGUAAACUGGUGAUUAUUGUAUUGAAUGCAAAUCUUUUUAUUAUUUUUCCAGAUAUAUUGAGUUUUAUAAACCAUUAAAAUAUUAUUUUAUGAAAUUUCCCUUCCUGGAUGAACAGAAUAUUGUUUUAUUAAAUCUUCUCUUAUUAGUGGAAUAUUUUUUACUUCUUUGUCUUUUCAUUUACUUGUUUUUUGUUAUAAUGAAAACUUUACUAGUGUUUGGUACCAUUGAGAUAACUUAUUACUGGAAAUUUUGUUUGCUUCCUGUGGGAUAUAUCUGGAAGUGGUCAUAGUCCAACCAUGUCCUUUUGAUGUUGUUAGCAUAUCAGUUAUUCUAUGUAUUGAUCUUUUCUUCUCCUGUAUUCAACACCUCUUUCUGAAAGGAUGUCUGAUCUUCCCAUAAUCGCUUUGAUGUAGAUGAUAUUUUUAUUCUAUCAGUGUAUACUAGACAGGAUUUUGAUGUGGCUUUGUAUUUGUAUAUUUAAAUACCAUGUCUUUAAAGCAUUAUUAGAAGAGAUAUUCUAGUUUCUUCUAAUGUCCCUUUUAAAAAAAAUAUAGCCAGUCCAAUAUCUCAAACUACUUUGAUUUUUGAACUUAAAUCAACUUUUAGUGCUACCUUGUUUAAUGGUAGUAGUAUUUUCUCAUUUCUACAUGUUCACACAAGUUUAUUAUAUAUAGUUUAUGGUCAUAUGUAUCUUAUAAAAAUUUUGAAGCCCAUCCCCAUGGAUUUAUUAUAAUACAGCUCUGAUAUAUCUUAAAGUUAACCCGUUUUCCGUAGAUGUUAAGGGCUUUACUGGUUGAGGUAACCUAUUUCAAAUGGUCUGUUGGGUUUUGUGGUACCUUGUCAAGAAUUCAAUAAGAAUUCUCAGGCUGUCUGUAUUUUCUUUUAGGACUUUGGAGAUCUCUCAAGUUGUACUGUUUUCUAGUAUUCCUGAGUAUAUUCCUUUGGUAACGUGAAAGUAAAUAGUUUAUAUUUGAUGAUUUUUUUUUUUUUUUUUUGAGACGGAGUCUUGCUCUGUCACCCAGGCUGGAGUACAGUGGUGAGAUCACGGCUCACUGCAAGCUCUGCCUCCCGGGUUCACGCCAUUCUCCUGCCUAAGCCUCCUGAGUAGCUGGGACUACAGGCGCCCGCCACCACACCCGGCGAAUUUUUUGUAUUUUUAGUAGAGAUGGGGUUUCACCGUGUUAGUCCAGGUGGUCUCAAUCUCCUGAACCUUGUGAUCCACCUACCUUGGCCUCCCAAAGUGCUGGGAUUACAGGCGUGAGCCACAGUGCCCGGCCUGUAUUUGGUGAUAUUUUAAAAAAUUCUACUUUGACCUUAAGUGCUUCAAGAAUUGUGUUCAGUUAGUAGUCCUUUUGUAAGACUAACUUUCAUAUGCUAUCUUUGCUCCAUGAGCUAUCAUAGUACUGUUUUCUUUCAUUACCCGUAAGAGUGGCUCUAUCACAGCAUUUACUGUUAAGGGCUACAGUUAGACCUCUUGUUAACUCUACUUUUAUUUGUGAUGGCUGUGUUUCACACUACCUUGAUUUAUAAAUGUAGUAAUGUGUUAAAUAACUAUAUGUUGUGGUCCCUUAAUACCUCUUUUGAUUGGUGAGGUAACAGUGAUGUGGAUGAUGAAAUAAAAACGUUUCCCCAAGUCACUAAACACAGUUUUCAAUUCAUUUUUUUUUACAUAUUUAAUUUACAUCUAACUACUGUUAGGUAUGCAGCCCGUUCCUUUUUGCCUUCAGUAGAAUAUAGUUAUAUAAGUAGUCUCAUUUAGAUUCUUGGGACAGAACGGCCUGUGUAUUGAUCUUUCUUUAAUGGCUUGGAACAGCUUCUAUAUAUUCUGACAGGUCUUGGAAGCAUGUUAAUAUCCGUGUGUUUAAUUGUCAUCUUCCUGCCUGGGAAGGCAGUAGAAGAAAGAAUCUACAUUUGUAUAGUCUGUAGUACAGGCUCUGUGCUGAUUGCAAGGCACUCUUGAGAGAAAUUCAUUCUUAUUUUGCAGAAGAAGAACUGAAACUUCAUUAAGUCAUUAAGCAACUUGCUCAGGUGGUGGAACUGAGCUUUAAAUAUGGACUUUUUCCAGUCUCAAUUCAGCAUUAUACUAGGCUGCCUCCAUGUGUUUUUCAAAGCCCCAUUCAAGUUUUACUUCUAUGGUAAACUAAUUUUACAUACACAAAUCUUUUCAUUUUCUGAACUUCCUUUAUGGCUUUACUGUCACCCCACUAGUAUUUGAUGUCUUAGCUAUUAACUAAUUCCUGAUUAUUUCACUUGUCACAUCAGGAACCCUAUCCUCUUAGUUCUCCCAUUGAGAUUUCACUGCUGGACUAAGAUUAUUCUUGAUUCGUAGUCAUUGGUUUCUGUUUCCAUUCAUUUUCAGCACUGAUUAUGUUAAUCGUAUUGCUUGAGUUUUUUCUUUGUUCAAUGUUGUUUAUUACAUUCAUUUUGUUUCAUAUACACACAUUUUUUUUUUUUAACUGGCAUUUUGAGGAUAUUGGUUUAAUGGAAGGAAAAAGGAAUGGUGCAAAGCACAUGGUAUUUGAAUUCCAAAGACCUUGACCCUCAGCAUUAGCAAGUCACUUGUUUUCUGAGCCUCAGUUUUCUUACUCUCAAAUGAGGUAAUAUCCGAAAGUACUUUGACAACACACUAAAGCCUGAUGCAGAUUUCCUUUUUGAAGUAAUUGUGCUGUUUCUAUUCAUAUUGGAUAUGGUAUUCUAUGGUAUUGGCUAUAGAUACAUACAUUUUAAAAUGUUAUUUAACAGCAUGUAAAUGUUCAUUUCAUGCCAUGUGAUCAUGUUCCCCUUUAUGAUUUUUUAAGGCUGUCUUACAAGCCUAACAGUGUACUAAGUCAUUAAAAGAUAUAUUUAAAGUAAAA